AGUCGGCAGGUCUGAGGCGGCGCUGUGUGUGUGAAGCGUACCUAGGGCGGGAGGCGACAUGGAGACAGGGGCGGCCGAGCUGUAUGACCAGGCCCUUUUGGGCAUCCUGCAGCACGUGGGCAACGUCCAGGAUUUCCUGCGCGUUCUCUUUGGCUUCCUCUACCGCAAGACAGACUUCUAUCGCUUGCUGCGCCACCCAUCGGACCGCAUGGGCUUCCCGCCCGGGGCCGCGCAGGCCUUGGUGCUGCAGGUAUUCAAAACCUUUGACCACAUGGCCCGUCAGGAUGAUGAGAAGAGAAGGCAGGAACUUGAAGAGAAAAUCAGAAGAAAGGAAGAGGAAGAGGCCAAGACUGUGUCAGCUGCUGCAGCUGAGAAGGAGCCAGUCCCAGUUCCAGUCCAGGAAAUAGAGAUUGACUCCACCACAGAAUUGGAUGGGCAUCAGGAAGUAGAGAAAGUGCAGCCUCCAGGCCCUGUGAAGGAAAUGGCCCAUGGUUCACAGGAGGCAGAAGCUCCAGGAGCAGUUGCUGGUGCUGCUGAAGUCCCUAGGGAACCACCAAUUCUUCCCAGGAUUCAGGAGCAGUUCCAGAAAAAUCCCGACAGUUACAAUGGUGCUGUCCGAGAGAACUACACCUGGUCACAGGACUAUACUGACCUGGAGGUCAGGGUGCCAGUACCCAAGCACGUGGUGAAGGGAAAGCAGGUCUCAGUGGCCCUUAGCAGCAGCUCCAUUCGUGUGGCCAUGCUGGAGGAAAAUGGGGAGCGCGUCCUCAUGGAAGGGAAGCUCACCCACAAGAUCAACACUGAGAGUUCUCUCUGGAGUCUCGAGCCCGGGAAGUGCGUUUUGGUGAACCUGAGCAAGGUGGGCGAGUAUUGGUGGAACGCCAUCCUGGAGGGAGAAGAGCCCAUCGACAUUGACAAGAUCAACAAGGAGCGCUCCAUGGCCACCGUGGAUGAGGAGGAACAGGCGGUGUUGGACAGGCUUACCUUUGACUACCACCAGAAGCUGCAGGGCAAGCCACAGAGCCAUGAGCUGAAAGUCCAUGAGAUGCUGAAGAAGGGGUGGGAUGCUGAAGGUUCUCCCUUCCGAGGCCAGCGAUUCGACCCUGCCAUGUUCAACAUCUCCCCGGGGGCUGUGCAGUUUUAAUGACCAGAAGGAAAGGAAACCCUCGCCGGUGGGGAGGCAGAGCCUUAUCCUCGGCUGCCCUUCUUGGCUCCCUGCAUUCCAGGGACUUGCUCGUCUUGUUUACCCCUAGCCAUCCUUUCUUUCAAGGGUGAACCAGGCCUUCCACCCUGACCUUGCAUCUCCAGACUGUUCCAGAGAAGGUGCGGGGCCAGCUGCUAUGUGGUGGCCGCUGUGGCUGACACUGAGUGAAGGUGUUUGAAAUGCAGGAGAGGAUAUCCCAGCAAAUUGGGAUCACAUGCUUUUGUCUCCACAGCAACCAGCCACUGCAGGCAGCAUGUCUUUCCUCCCCUGCUCUCUGCUUGCUGUUGUUUUGACGCUAUUCUGCUUGCAUGUCUUCUGGUUGGGAUGUGGAGUUGUUGCUGGACUCUCAGGCGAAGCUGAAGUCAUUGAAGUGUGUGAAGCUCUGUGCUUGCAUGAGGGCAAGCAAGGAAUGGCUGUGCCUGAGGCUGCUCUGGGAAACUCCUUGCCCCUUGACCUCUUUUGAGAGCAUUCACGUGGUCUUCUUGCUCAUCCCCUUAUAAAUGUGCUUUGCCUGCCUCAGCCUCAUGGUCAGAGCAGUGGAGACUGGAGCCCUGUUUGCACGUUCUAGUUGUUCGGAGAAAGCCUAGGUUCUGGGCUCAGGUCCAGAUGCAGCGGGGAUUCUGUUCUCUGACUGUGGCGACCUUGCUUUGGUUCUUGUUGAAGUGAACCAAGCCCGGCCACCACGCAUGGCAUGCUGUGCUUGGCUCCCCAUAAGACGUCCUCUUUGGGUGCACGGUGUCAAAGUGUGGGCAGGAGUGGAGAGCUGGUGCCCUCAGGAGGAGACCACAGCAUGUCCAUCAGCUCAGCAGAGCUCGACAGCCACAAGUCCUGAGAAGCUUUGACCUUGAAGGGCUUCUGGGAGAGGAGGAAUUUCUGCAUGGGGCGUGAAGGCACACUGUCCCACCACAACUGAACCAGAAGAGAGUGAAGACUCCCCUCUUCCCAUCCUCUGUGCCAGGUGCCAGACUGUGCUCCUUGGAACUUAUGGCCCAAUCUUACCUGUUCUCCAGGGACUGGUCACUGCCUCAGGACCCCCAAGCCUAUGCCCUGAGCCAUGGCUGCUGACUGACUCCAGCCAAGGUGCAAAGACGAGAUUAUGAGACAGGUCCUCAGGCCUGUGUUCCAAGUACUCACAGGGGCUCUGGGUGCCCAUCGCCGGGAGUAUGGUUCAGCUGCCACCGGCACUGUCCAUUUGCCUGUCUGUCAAGCUCAGAGCAUGGAUAAGCCACACAGCAGGGCAGUGCACCCUGGCACCAUGCACGGCCAGCAAGAAUCAAGGCCCGCAGAUGCUAAGAGGGCCUAUUGUCAGGGGAAGGUCCCCGCUCCUGCACACUCUCUAUGGAUACUUGGGUUGUGGGGGCUCUCUUGGAGAGUAAGUUUGUGGUUUGUUUCUGGUUUACAGUGGUGGCUGACACCCCUUGUAAGAAAGCAUUCCUGGGAAGUCUUCUGUGGGUCCAAACAUGUUGCUCCGAUCAUCACAGGAGAGCAAAAGGCCCUAGAUACCCCCUUUGGAAUGUGAGAGUCUUGUUGUCUGAUAUUUGCCACUGAGCUGGUGAAGCCCCUCUAAAGAGAUCUCGACCCUGGGGAGCAGAAUUCUUGUCAUCUAUGAGGGGUCCUGAGAAAGACUUGUCAUUUUUUUUCCUGGAGUUCUUCCCAUUGAGGUCCUAGGAUUUGCACACCACUGUCCCACAAGAGCUUUCCUGCCUAAUGAAAGGAGGUCUUGUGGUGUGUGUCUCCUCUCUUCUCUAUAGUUCCCGAGUUGGCCCCCAUUGCAGCCCCCACCCUGUGGGUAGUCUUCCAGAAGUGAUGCAGUGGUGUGAGAUGCCCUACACCUUGUUAUUUGGGAGACUUUGAGAGUCAUUCACUUCCAUGGUGACUAGUGUUUGUUUUGCCUGAUUUUAUAUUCUGUGUUGCAUUUCUCCCCACUCCCUGCCCUGCUUUAAUAAACAGCAAACCAAUAUCUAGGAAGAAUGACUGAGGGAUAGUAUUGGGUAUUGGCCCCAUGGCAGGAACAGCCACUUGCAUCUGGUCCCGGUGCCACACUGCGGUGCUUGGUGUGGUUGUGGAGCCUGUCCCUGCGCGCCUUGCUCCCGUUGAGCCACGCUGUCUGGUGGGUGAUUCUCUGCCCUGAGCCACCACCCUGGACUGGCCCAGUCUCCAGAGCUGGCACACCCUGCCUGUUUUCUCUUUUUAGACACAACAGCCGCAGUUUGGCCAGCCACUAAGUCCCACCAGCUGAGGUCCGAGGAAAGCGGGGUGACUCAUUUCCCUUGUCCAGGGCCCGAGGAGAGUGAGGUGUCCAGCCUGCAAAGCUAUUCCAGCUCCUUGGUGUUGGUUUGCAAUAAAUUGGUAUUUAAGCAGUUCUGGGUCUGCGUGUGACAUUUGCUGCUGAGACAGUUCUGUCUGUGCAUGGUCAUUAUUGUUGCAUUCUAGCCUUGAGGUCCCAGGCCAACGUACACAGCAAACACCAGCAUGGGGAAUUCUUAGGGGUUGUUUCCCAUCUGGUCUGAAUGCACUGGGCAAGAUCUCAAUACAGCUUUAGAAAUCCUGUAAGAUUUUGACCAGUGGGGAGAAAAAGAAUGUAGCUAUAGAUCUUACAUCCUUUCAAACAGGUUCUGGAAUUCUGUAGUUACUGGAAAGCUUAGGGUGAGUGCAGAGUUGGGAAUGAUUCCACUGAAGGGCCACCUUUGCCCACCAGGCUCCAAGGCCCUCCUUGGUCUCCAGGUGCAUACCUGCUGUUAACUUUGCUGAGCCCUCGCAAUGGGCUUCCUCCAGGACAUAACGCCGUGUCUGACACAGAAGUCUCCCAGGUGGCUGGCCACCUGCUUCUUCCUCAGUCAGAUCUUUGACUCUCCUUCUCUGUGCCCACCCCAUCUCCAGCCUCCUCUGACCCUGCUCACCCCUGGGGACAGGACCUAGGGGUGUGAGAAGUACUUGGCUGAAUAAAGACUGUUUCAAAGGCAAUCCUUAGAAUUGCCUAGCAUACUCCCAGGGCCAGAAAUAACCCGCCAGAAAGGAGAGGCGUAUUUGCCCCUGAAGAGUGCAGGAGGGAGAACAGUUGAGAAGUGUUUUGUGUGGAAAUGUGUCCAAGAGGCGUCAGCUGCUGCACAGAGAACUCACUGCCCAGAACACUGCGCUUGGGGAACAGACCUCACCCCCACCUCAAAUCUGCUCUCCACUGGGCCUGUUGGCAGCCAGCUCAGCUGGGGAAGGGACAGCAUGACUCGCUUUGUCGAUGAAAAGCACGAAGUUGUCAGCACAGAACCUGGCCAGUCCUUGAGAAACUCCCUCCUUGGUGGUCAGAGGUCAAGCAGCCCAUGUGGCCCACGGUCCUGAAGAACUGGGCUAUGUCCCUGAGGCUCCUCUCUACCGUCUGACUGUGGGGUCUGGGGAACAGGCAUUUAAACCAGGCUGCUGCCCUGGGGAGUGCCCACUGGACGCCAGGGUGCCCCAUAGGGACAGGGUCACAAAGCCCUGGGGCUUCCCCUGCCAGUCCUGGUGAGGACAGUGUGGUCACUAUCUCAGAGAGACGAAAAAUGAAUAUUCUGUCAUUUCAGACUAAACUACUCACCCAGCUCACACUAAUAUGGAUUUGUUAAUUUUACCUUUUUUUUUCUUUCCAACUUUAGGUUCAAGGGUUGUUACAUGGGUAAAUUGGAUCAUAGGGGUUUGGUGUACAGAUAAUUUUGUCACCCAGGUAAUCAGCAUGAUACCUGAUAUGUAGUUUUUCAGUCCUCACCUUCCUCCCACUCGGUUUUAUUUUUUAGUACUGAAAGUUUAACAGAUUGGUCUUACCUCAGAGGGAGGGAAGAAACCCCCCCAUCGCUGGGCUCCUUGGUGUGACAGGGGUCUGGUAGGGGUUUUCAAUCCCACCACCCAUUCCUCCACACCAAAUGCCUGAAGUCCCCACUUUGCACAGGGAGACAGCAUCGUGCCAGGGAAGAGAGGUCAGGCCCGGCUACCCCUCACAACUUCCUGCUUCCCCCUCAGAGGGUGAUGGGGAGACCAGAGCCCAUGGCAGGAUGAACUGUCACUGAACCCAGCUGGCACAGGUCUGCCAGAACACUCUGGGGGUAUGCGCUGGGCUUUCUGGGUAAACCCCUGGCAAGCUGGCGUUUGCUGUCUUCUCAGUGCUGAUGGAGAUAGGCACACAUGGGGUGUGGGAAUGUGGCCACCCUCAGGCAGGUUCACGAGGGUACUGUCAGGCGCUCAGGUGUAUGCCGCCUCCUGUCAGGCAGGGCUGAGGCUAUUCUCCCUGGAGAAGGACAGCUUAGGAAACACUUGCAGGAAAGCUGCCUGGACCUGGGAGGUGACCCUGGCCAGCCUCCCUGCUGCCUCUCUCAGUCCUAGGCCUUCUUCCCCAGAGCUGGUCAGGGCCUGAGGGACUUUGUAGUCUAACCCCUCAUUGUGCUACAAUCACAGGAGUAAGUAACACUCCCAAGGCCAUGUGGCUGGUGACUCGGGGGGCCCAGGUCCAGGAUCCUGCCCCAUCUGCAGGCCAGUGGUUCCUUGUCUCCUAUUUGCUUCUUGGAGCAGCCUCCUCAUAAGCCAACAGCUCCUUCACCUGAGCCCAGUCACUUUGCGCUCCUCCCCAGAACCAAAGAGCAAGACCAUCUGCCCCAGGUACAGUCCUGGCCAUGCCACACUCUCUGUGGCAUCAUGACCAAGGUGAGUGGCAGAUACUGAAAUCAUCCAGGGCCACUGCAGGCCCCAUUCCCAGUGGACUGUUCAUCAAGGGACCCUGUCUCAGGCCAUCUCAGCCAACCUUGUUGCCCAGCACAGGUCUGGCACAUUGGAGAUGAUCUGUGUUGGAUGGGGAAGGCAGAGGGAGGAUCCUCCAGCAUUGAUCACCCAUCAAAACCCUCAACAACCCAGACAUUGCCGCUGCACUGACCCCAUGCUAUGAGGAGGUCACUCAGGCUGUUAGGAGCCUGCUGACUCAGGCAUUGGGCUGGGGCCCUGCCUGCCUUGUCUGCCUGCCAGCGGAGCACUGCCCCAAGCCCUUCUUACUGCAGAGACAGGCUCUUGCCUCCCAGUGUGCACUUUGUGCAAGACACAGGCAGGUAAGGGUCUACCAGAGGACAGGAAGUGUUGUUGGGGCACUGUGGGGUUUGGAGGAGGCCCCUCUAGCAGGGAAAGCGAGCCCUAACCUCUGCUGGACUAGGGAGUUUAGGAAGCUGCUCUGGUUCAGGGAACUGGGGAUCCAGAUAACUGGGGAUCAAGGCCAUCUUGUGACCCCAGUGGUGGUCCCUAGUGGGACUGCUGAGCUCCAGCCUGAGAGUUCAUGAACUCAACAGUGAUUGCUUGUGGGUACUAAUGACCCAGUGUGUGGAGACCUCAUUUACCAGGUGUGCCUAGCCUGCAGGCAAAUCCCAAGGCAGUGACCCUUAGGGAAGAGACAGCGUUUGGGGUCAUCAAAGGCUGGGAAACCCAGGUACCUGUCAGGGAAUGGGCUACAGACUGGAGCUAAGCCUUAAGGUGGGGAAGAUUCCAGCACCCCUGAGUGACCACCUCUUUUGGUAAUGCAAAGAAGGGAUUUUGUGACUCCAGGGUGACAUUUCUAAGCUUGGCAUCAUGCAGGGUGGGCUUGGGCUCAAUAUGGGUGACUGUUAGUCUAGGGCUGUCUCAAUGAGGCUGUCCAGGCAGAAAGGCUUACACACCUGGCAGGCAGAGGGUCUAGAGAGGAAGGGGCAACAGGCCUAAGGAGGGGACAGCCAGGCAAGGAGGUAGAAUAGGCCUUGUCUGGACAGUGGUCACCUGUUAGGUCCACAGCUUGUCCUCCCUGGCCUGACCAGCCAGGUGAGGAGAGAUCCAAACCAUCCACCUGAAAGCAUUCAGGGUGCCUGAUGACAAGACCCCAGCCACUGUGGGCUCUCAUGUCCUGGUAGGAAGGUAUACCUAAAGCAGGUGGACCUGGUAGUGGUGGACGCUGUCUGCCUCCCCGGGGCUUGUCUGUUUAUGCCAGACCGUUUUCCCAUUUGCUUCCACCUCCAGCUCAGAGAGGAAUCACCUUCACACCUCUGCUAAAACUAACCCAGCUCUGCACCCACCAUUCCCCACUGUGCAACACCUGCUACUGGAGAACCCUGCCCCCUCAAAUACACGUCAUCCUCAGGGCCCUGCGAUGUGCUGUGGUCUCCCUGCCACCAUUCAAGGGGCCACAGCCAGGUCCAGCCUGUCUUCCCUGGCACCAGGCUCUAUGCAGUGGGGGAAACUCGGGCACCCCUAAACUAUUCUCCAGUGUUCUCACCAGAGGUGGUCAGCCAUGUGAUGGCAAGAGUCACUUCUUAAGCUUUUGCUAUCCCCAGAAACUUAAAGCAACACCAACCACACCCAAAAGUCAAGUGAUAUCCAGACAGCAACAGUAGAGCAUUAACUGAGUGCAGGGCCGUGGUGACUCCUCGACACUCCAGGCUCUCCUGCUGGUAACCUCCCAUUGGCAGAGCCAGGCACUCAGCAAAGCCCUGGACAGUCAGCAGCCUCCUGAACAGGCUCUGCUGUCCCCACUCACGACUUCAGAGCAGCUAGGACUCCUGUGACCACCCCUGUCCCCUGUUCCCCCCCACCCCGCCCCGCCCCGCCAACUGCCUCAUCUCUGUCCCAAGAUAACUGCUCUCCAGAAUUUUCCAUGAUAUGGUCAUUUUAAAAGUUUUUUUUUUUUUUGAGACAGAGUUUUUCCUGUGUUGCCCAGACUGGACUCAAACCUCUGGGCUCAAGUGAUCCUCCUGCUUCAGCCUCCCAAGUAGCUGGGACUGUAAGUGUGCACCACUGUGCCUGGCUUGAUGGUGUCAUUUUUCACUGUACGUGUAUUUGUAAACCGUAUAAAUCAGUA